AUGGCACUAGCCAAUCAGAAGAAGGCGCCGCAGAGGGUGGAGCUUAGCGAGGAAAUCCUACAAGCAUCUGGAAACGACCAUUUUCGUCAAACUGCGGGUAGAGUCUUUCUCCCCGACAGGUGGAUCAGUAGUACAGUCCGUAAAAUUGGUUUUGGAGCUUCGCUGAGCCUCCUGGGCGUAGGGUUCCCGGGAAAGUGUGGAGUGAGCCGCAGCGCCCUGGGGUCUGGCGGGGUGACUGAAAGAGGGAAUGGAAGCUGGAUGAAGAGGGUUGAGGGAGCUUUGGAAGCCAGACCCGGCGCUGUCCUAGGGGCUAGCACUACCCACGGGCGGAGGGAGGAAGGGGGCGGUGGCAGGAGGCAGGAGGGGGGUGGAGCGCGGAGUGGGUUUUCGGGUGCCGGAGAAGAAAGGGGGCGUUAUUUGAAAGAAGGGACCGGGACCUGGCGGGAUUUAGGGGCGAUGUGGACCCGGGGCGACCUGUGUAAUGGAUGGGUUGUGCGAGCAACACAGUUUUGGGGUGACCCAAGAACGGAGUAUCAUAGGGAGUGGUUAGGCUCCAGAUGGAGGUGGGUGCAAGGAGCACAGUCUUUGGACCUGGACCCAGCGGUCUGCGACGACGUGCUCCGCUCACUGCUGAGUGAUCUAGUGCAAGUUCCCGCACCUCUCUGAGCCUCAGUUUCCACAUCUGUAGAUGGGAAUAACAAUCAUAUACGACGCACAAGAUUGCUGUGACGAUUUAGUUAGAGGAGAUGAUGCGUGUGCCUCCCUGCCUCGUGAUA